CCUUUUCGCAACCCUAACGGGAGAGAAGUGAUGGAAGAAGGGUAGCCGGAAGAGUUUCCUCAAAAUACCAUAGGGGUUUUAAAUUAUUAGUACGUAUUUAAACUCAUCUACUUUCACGUUGUCCCGUUGAACGUCACUUCCGCUUAGGGGCGGACACGUCCCAAACCUGUGGCGGGAGUUGGAGAUUCUGCGGCGAAUACGCCAGGUGUGACUGGCUGGAAGUGGCGUGGCUGGAUCAUCAUGCCUAGGGUUCAUAACAUAAAAAAGUCUCUUACACCUCACAUUUCUUGUGUGACAAAUGAAUCUGAUAAUCUGCUGGAUUUUUUGCCUGACAGACUAAGAGCAAAGCUACUUCCAUUCCAGAAAGAUGGCAUCAUUUUUGCCCUCAAAAGAAAUGGCAGGUGUAUGGUGGCUGAUGAAAUGGGUCUAGGAAAGACAAUCCAGGCAAUUGGAAUUACUUACUUCUAUAAAGAGGAAUGGCCUCUGUUAAUAGUGGUCCCUUCGUCUCUGAGGUACCCUUGGACAGAAGAAAUUGAAAAAUGGAUCCCAGAGCUAAGUCCAGAAGAAAUCAAUGUUAUUCAGAAUAAAACUGAUGUUAGGAGAAUGUCGACCAGUAAAGUGACAGUUCUGGGUUAUGGUCUCUUAACCGCAGAUGCAAAGACUUUGAUAGAUGCACUGAAUAAUCAGAACUUCAAAGUAGUUAUAGUGGAUGAAUCACACUACAUGAAAUCCAGAAAUGCAACUCGCAGCAGGAUUUUAUUGCCAAUAGUACAGAAAGCCAGACGAGCCAUUCUUCUUACAGGAACACCAGCUUUAGGAAGGCCUGAAGAGCUUUUUAUGCAGAUUGAAGCUCUCUUUCCACAAAAAUUUGGAAGAUGGACCGACUAUGCAAAAAGAUACUGUAAUGCACACAUCAGAUAUUUUGGUAAAAGACCUCAGUGGGAUUGUAGAGGGGCAUCAAAUCUUAAUGAACUUCACCAGCUAUUAAGUGACAUAAUGAUUAGAAGAUUAAAGACUGAAGUUUUAACCCAGCUACCCCCUAAAGUCAGACAGCGUAUUCCAUUUGAUCUUCCAUCAGCAGCUGCCAAGGAAUUGAAUACCAGCUUUGAAGAGUGGGAAAAAAUAAUGAGAACUCCAAAUUCAGGUGCCAUGGAGACAGUCAUGGGGUUGAUAACUCGCAUGUUUAAACAAACUGCUAUUGCCAAGGCAGGUGCUGUAAAGGAUUAUAUUAAGAUGAUGCUUCAGAAUGAUUCGCUUAAAUUUCUGGUUUUUGCUCACCAUUUAAGCAUGCUCCAAGCUUGCACAGAAGCAGUCAUCGAAAAUAAGACUCGUUACAUUAGGAUAGAUGGAAGUGUUUCAUCUUCAGAAAGAAUACAUCUGGUUAAUCAGUUUCAAAAGGAUCCUGACACUCGCGUGGCUAUCCUAAGCAUUCAGGCUGCUGGCCAGGACCUGUAUGACAAGGUGGCCUGGGGGAAAAGAACUCUUGUCUCAGGACUUUUUAUGGAGUGCUUCUGUUUUGUCCCUUAGGAUUAAGUUUGAAGGGAUUAACAUUUACUGCAGCAAGUCAUGUUGUAUUUGCUGAGUUGUACUGGGACCCUGGACAUAUAAAACAAGCAGAAGACCGAGCUCACAGAAUUGGCCAGUGCAGUUCUGUGAAUAUUCACUACCUUAUUGCAAAUGGAACCCUAGACACCCUUAUGUGGGGAAUGUUGAAUCGCAAGGCUCAAGUUACAGGGAGCACACUGAACGGUAGGAAAGAAAAAAUUCAGGCUGAGGAAGGUGAUAAGGAAAAAUGGGAUUUCCUGCAGUUUGCUGAAGCUUGGACUCCAAAUGACAGUUCUGAAGAGUUAAGGAAGGAAGCUUUGUUCACUCACUUCGAAAAAGAAAAACAGCAUGAUAUUCGAUCAUUUUUUGUACCACAACCUAAAAAAAGACAGUUGAUGACCUCCUGUGACGAAUCAAAGAGAUUCCGGGAGGAAAAUACUGUAGUGUCAUCAGACCCUACAAAAACAGCUGCAAGAGAUAUCAUCGAUUAUGAAAGUGAUGUUGAACCUGAAACGAAAAGAUUGAAAUUGGCUGCCUCGGAAGACCACUGCAGUCCGUCGGAAGAGACACCAUCCCAGUCCAAGCAAAUCCGAACUCCACUCGUGGAAAGUGUACAGGAGGCCAAGGCCCAGUUAACCACCCCAGCCUUUCCUGUAGAGGGCUGGCAAUGUAGUCUCUGCACCUAUAUCAAUAAUUCAGAGUUACCUUAUUGUGAAAUGUGUGAGACUCCUCAAGGCAGUGCUGUUAUGCAAAUAGAUAGCCUCAACCAUAUCCAGGAUAAAAACGAGAAGGAUGAUUCUCAGAAAGACACCUCCAAAAAGGUUCAAACUAUCUCAGACUGUGAAAAACAAGCCCUUGCACAGUCAGAACCUGGCCAGUUGGCUGACAGCAAGGAAGAAACACCAAAAAUUGAGAAAGAAGACGGACUUACAUCCCAGCCAGGUAAUGAACAGUGGAAGAGUUCAGACACUUUGCCAGUGUAUGACACCUUAAUGUUCUGUGCAAGUAGGAAUACUGACCGGAUUCACAUCUAUACUAAGGAUGGAAAACAGAUGAGCUGUAAUUUCAUUCCUCUGGAUAUAAAAUUAGACCUUUGGGAAGAUUUACCAGCAAGCUUUCAGCUGAAACAAUAUCGCUCACUGAUUUUGAGAUUUGUUCGAGAAUGGAGUAGUCUAACUGCCAUGAAGCAAAGGAUAAUCAGGAAAAGUGGACAGCUAUUCUGUAGCCCAAUUCUUGCUUUGGAAGAGAUCACAAAGCAACAAACCAAACAAAAUUGCACCAAAAGAUACAUAACCAAAGAAGAUGUUGCCGUAGCCUCAAUGGACAAAGUGAAGAAUGUUGGGGGCCAUGUCCGUCUGAUCACAAAGGAGUCCAGGCCACGGGAUCCUUUCACAAAAAAACUUCUUGAAGAUGGAGCCUGUGUCCCAUUUCUAAAUCCAUACACAGUCCAGGCAGAUCUCACUGUGAAGCCCUCUACAUCCAAAGGCUAUUUGCAAGCUGUGGAUAAUGAAGGAAAUCCACUUUGCCUUCGCUGUCAGCAACCCACUUGCCAGACUAAGCAAGCAUGUAAAGCGAACUCUUGGGAUUCACGGUUUUGCUCUCUGAAAUGUCAGGAAGAGUUUUGGAUUCGAUCUAAUAACAGUUACCUGAGAGCCAAAGUAUUUGAAACUGAACAUGGUGUGUGUCAGCUCUGUAAUGUGAACGCACAAGAACUCUUUUUACGUCUGAGAGAUGCCCCUAAAAGUCAGAGGAAGAAUCUUCUGUAUGCUACCUGGACUUCAAAGCUCCCAUUAGAACAGCUAAAUGAAAUGAUAAGAAACCCAGGGGAAGGACAUUUCUGGCAGGUGGAUCACAUCAAGCCAGUGUAUGGGGGAGGAGGACAGUGUUCCCUGGACAACCUGCAGACUCUCUGCACAGUCUGUCACAAAGAGAGAACUGCCAGACAAGCUAAGGAAAGAAGCCAGGUGAGAAGACAAUCUCUAGCAUCAAAGCAUGGAUCAGACAUCACACGAUUUUUGGUAAAGAAGUAAAGUAGAAAAAUAUAUGAAUGAAUGACAAAUGGUUUACAUGUGGAAGACUUUAAUACAGAAGUUUUCCAUGUUUGUUUAAUAUAUCGAGAGUAAAAAUUUUCAGAACAAAAAUCAAGAAUUCAAAUUCUCUUCUACUAAUUACUUUUAGUAUUAAAUACAUUUUGAAAGUACUUAACAGAAACUAAGAUACAAUACUGAAUAUUUCUGUGGUCUUUUUGAUUUGAUUCAGACUCGCAAUUAUGUUUCAGCAAUGUUUUGUAAAGCUCUUUACCCCUAAUAUGCCUAAUCACUGUAUUGUGCAUAGAUUGUGUUUAAAAAAUGUACUCUCAAUUACCUAAAAAUGCUUCUGGAUUAGUAUUGUUCUGGACUGUCAUAGGUAUGAGUGGAACAUUGCAAAACCUUAUGGGAAAUUUCAGACGCAAAUCAUUAUUUGGGAAUUCUGGGCCAAGCAUGACCAGCCUGCUUAGGAUUCAAGAGAGACUGUCCACUAAAUACCUCCAGAAUGAGCUAGGGGCACACAUUUUGGGUGUUGCUUUUCUUGCUUUAUUUCUUAGCUAGUCAUCUUUAUCAAAAAUAUCCUUUUCAAAAUGAGGUACCUAUGGUGUUUGUGGACAAUUUGGGGGUUCUGUGUAAAGUAAUUGUUAAAACUAUUAAAUAACUGAAAACAUAAAAUGUAAAAUGCCACUUAAGCUUGAUUUUUUAGAUCUUUUUUUAAAAAAUGAAUAAAACUAGGCUUACUGUUGGCUGGGCGCGGUGGCUCACGCAUGUAAUCCCAGCACUUUGGGAGGCCAAAGCGGGUGGAUCAUGAGGUCAGGAGAUAGAUCGAGACCAUCCUGGCUAAUACGGUGAAACCCCAUCUCUACUAAAAAUACAAAAAAUUAGCCGGGCAUGGUGUUGUGCACGUGUAAUCUCAGAUACUCGGGAGGCUGAGGCAGGAGAAUUGCUUGAACCCGGGAAGCAGAGGUUGCAGUGAGCCGAGAUCACGCCAUUGAACUCCAGCCUGGGCGACAGAGCGAGACUCCGUCUCAAACAAACAAACAAACAAAAAAAAAAACUAAGCGUACUAUCAAAAUACACUUUGUCUUCUGGUUCUCAUUUUCUGUUUUUAAAACCCUGUGUUAUUAAAGGUAUGUUUCUGGUACUUAUUUUAAAAAGAGUGAUGAUGACAAAACACUUUAUAAUAAGGCAUAAUCAGAUGGUUAUAUGCAUUUAAAUAUACAAUAAUAACAUUAAAAUGUAAUUGACAUAAAAUAAGAGUGACGAUGAAACAAACCCAGGGCCUAGUCCUGCAAUAUGUCAGAAUCAUGAGGGCAAAGAGUCAGAACUAUACAAAAUACAGGACCGAGGAAGAAUUACAUUCCCAAAAGGGAGCUGUUUGUAAAUACUAUUAGGACAUAUACCUCUUUAGUUUGAGCAUUUUCCCACGUUAAUUAAUAGCUAGUGUUUUACAACAUAAAGGACUUGUUUUUAGAAAGAUUAUACAAUCAAAGAUUAUACAACCACAGUUGUUCCUCAGUUUCUAUUUCAUUGUAUGAGAUCAAGUCAUGUUGGUUAUUUUAUAAAUGAAGUUGGGCUUUCUUUGGCCUCCUUUCUGCUUAGUUGGUCAGGUGCUCUUUGCAGUUUUCUGCCUCAUUUCCAAGGUAACCUAGGAUUUGUCACGGUUGAGAGCCAAGAAGCAGGCACGCUGCCUUUCCUCCAGCAUGGGGUUUUGCAAGCGAGGUCUAAGUAGGUCAAAUUUGAGGGGAACUUGCUCUUCAGAUCACACUAAGGUGAUAAUUCUAAGGAGAAAGUUCUCAGAUGUAAGAACUGUGUGAUGGUUUGAGGUGAAACAAUCCAUGAAGAUAGGCUCAGUCUAUACCAGGUUUCAGAAUUCUGACUAAUUAAAAAUGCCGUAAGGAGCAUUGAGCAUUUGCUGUACAGGACACUGACUGGCCCGUCCCCAUCCCUUCCUGACAUGUCUCAGAGCUUUGUGUCCUGCCUUCCCCUAAUUUGGUCUGCAUUACUUGUGGGGCACAUUGAGAUGAAGGGUUCUGAGACAGAAAAUAAAGAUAGAGAUUGAUCUAAUAACCGAGACCGAAAGGGCAUCUUGAGGACUGUUCUUUCCUCCUCACAAUCUGAAACAGAAGCUCCCCACUAUGUAUUGCAAAUGGGAGGUUAUGACAGAGGGACACAGAAAGUGUCAGAGCAAGUGGCAGAUCCUGAGUGCAGAAGGAAGUGCAGAUGCCCCAGGAAGAAGACAGCUGCUGCCACUCAGGAGAUGGAGAUGGAGUGAAAACACAGGUGGGUACAAUGAGUGUAAAAGGAUAGGCCUGGCUCUGAAAAGACUCAGAGAAGCUGCAAGAUACAGUUUAGGCUAAGAAAACAACAACAAAAAAGGGCUCUGGCCAGGUAUGAUGGCACUUGCUUGUAGUCCUAGCUACACAGGAGGCUGAGGUAGGAGGGUCACUUAAGCCCAGGGGUUCAUGACCAGCCUGGGUAACACAGCAAGGCCCCAUCUCAAAAAAGAAAAAAGGCUCUGGGUCCAGGGAACAGAGCUGGGAAGUGGUAGGUGACGAAGGAACUCGCUUACGAUAGGGAACCAUAUGAAAAUAUGCCUGUGGGUAGGGGUAGGGUGGGGAGGACUUCCGGAGCAUGGUGGGCUCACACACUCAAACCUUGCACAGCCAGCAUCAGGCUGGCCUGCCUUCCUGUUCCCGUCACUGGGUGACAUUGAUCCCAGACACAUUCUGAUGACUAGUAAAGUUGCUUUUAGUAGCCCCAGAGCCAGGAGGAAUAAUUCAUAUGGAAUUUUUAAAGACGCCCACUCUUGGCGUUAAUUACAGCCCAACGUACAUUUCUUGGGGAGAUUUUCCUGUGACAAGUGAAUACCCUCUACAUUUUCUUAACUGGAUGGGAAAAGGAUUUUAUGCCCAUACAUCUUGCUAAUAAACCAAAUCCCUUCUUCAGAUUCUUGAGUGAAACAUUUAAAAUGUAGUUUCUUUAGAAAUAAAAGUAUGAGGCAUUUUAAAUUAUAUGACAGACAAAAAAGUCAAUGCUCUUGAGCUCUUUACAGUAAAUAGGUUGUGUUUACUCAUAGGAUACAGAAUCAUGGAUAUCAAACAUCAAAAAUAAAUUAUAAAAAUAAUGUCUCAUUUUCUGUUGCAUAUUAUUAGCCUGUCUCUCAUUCCACCAUUUGUUCUUUUGAACUGGAAAAUUGUGGGCUCCUAGUCACUGCACUAAUCUAUCUGAAUAUCCAACUACCAGAAAGGGUUUAUCCCAUCUCAAGUUUGUCAGUUGCUUUAUAUCGUUAAGGGUGUUUUUGCCACCCUGGUUGUGUUCAUAAUUACCAUUGAGAAAUGUCACUGUUAUUAAAAUACAUUCUGUGUUCCAACUA